GCUGGAUUCGAAACGCUUCCUGGUGCUCCUGGGCCUGGCGGUUGAGCCCGGGGAGCUAGUCUUUGCUUGGGUAAAGAAAGAGGACUUUCCUUUUUUUUUUUCCUUUUGAGAAAAUUCAGAAAUUUGGAGGCACAGUAGUUAGGAUUCAGGCCAAACUGGUAAAUGACGAAGGGGCUUCUUCCAGAGCCAAGGAGGAAGGGUUGUCCGGGUAAGUCCCGCGGGACGUGGAGAGACGGCGCCGCCCGGGUCCUCCCACUGAUUCCUUUGACCAUCUGGCUUACGGACGAGCUCUUUGUUCGCUGCUCCUCCGAAAACGCCUUCAAUGACUCCCUUUGAAUAAAGUAGGAAGUCCGAACCGAGCCGCCAGGCCGCGACUUGGCCCCUGUUUUCCACUCGCGAGGGCCCUGCGUCACCCCGCCUCGGGAAAGCUGCGCGUUCUCCGGCCGCUUGCGCUUGGCCGAAGCUGCUGGGUCCCGCUGUGCUUCCCCCGGGCAUGCGAUGGGGAUAAUUCCCACGCCUCGCUCAAAGCCAUCCCGGGAGAGCCCUCCCUGGUCCCCAUAGGCACAGUUGGGUGUUCCCUUUUCCGUGUUAACCUUGUAUUUCGGAUAUAGUUCUGUUAUAGUAAUUACUUUAAGGUAUUGUAGUUAUUUACAAUCAGUCUUUCCCCCACGGUAACCUAGAGUGUAAACCCCCUAAAUAAACGUCAGAAGUAAUGAAGUCUUAACUUCCUUGGCUUAGGUUUCAGCGCCCUUCUCAACCCCACACUCCCGCUUCAGUCUUUACACAACCCUUCCCAUGAAUAUGCUGACCUAACAAGUAACCUACUUUUCAUACUCCAAAAUCUUCUCUUCUGUGUGGGGAAAAUAAUGCAUUGACUGCCACCUCACUCCACCUCCAAAUAAAUUGAUGUUGAAAUUCUGGCCUCCGGUAAUGGAAUUCUUUACAUCAAAGUCACUUUUUAUUUCUAAAAGUAAUCACAUAUAUAUUAUAUUCCUACUGUGGCCCUUGCCAUGGAUCAACGAAAAAUAUGACAUAGUCAAAAUAGACCAAAACAUCUGGCCUUGUUGUAACCAAUGGGAAACACGGUUGGGAGGUCCCUACUUACAUGUCACUUGCUUCAGGAACCGUUCCUUGAUUCCUAAGUGGGGGACCUUUUUUCCUAAAUACAACUAUAGCUUGCUUUCUUACCUCUUAAGCCCUUUUUAUCUGCAGUCUCACUUACCCUACUAAGGUCUUUAAAUGCAGGGCUUGAUCUUCCAUUAUUGUAUCUCCAGCACCUAUAAAGCUUUCCUGUUAAAUAGUAGACAUUUAAUAAGUAUUUAUUGAUAAACGUGAAGUAUGCCUCAACGUUUAGGCUAAAUUCAUAUGAAAAUAAAAUUGAAAAAAUAAUUUUAAAGAACAGCAUUAGUUACUGAGAUUAUGUGGUAAAUCCCUUAAAAUAUAAUCUUGCAUUGAAAUAGUUUUCACCAUUUACCAGUCUUUAUAUGAAUAUAUACUCAUCUAAAUGGAAAUUGGGAAAUUUAAGCAUUUUCUGCUUUUCCGAAGUAAAUUUUCUAAUGUUUUUCUUAAAGCUGAACUAAAUUGCAAAACUUGCUUUAAUAAAGUGUGUAUUUUUGCAUCAGUUAAGCCCCUGACCUCUUUAUGUUCUUUAAAUUUGAUUCAUUAGUGAAAUUAACAAGGUUCUGUGUUUUUCUCACCUCAUUCAGUUUUAUAAUUAACCAAUAAAAGCUUAUUAGCUUUUAAGGAAGUUUUAGGAACUUAAAUUGAUUUAUGGGCACCAUAUGGUUACAUCAAAGGACUUGUUUUUGUUUUAACUGGAAGUGGAUUCUUAAGUCCUUUAAGAUGGAAAUUUAUGUUCUUUCUAUUAUACCAAGCAAUACUUUCUGAAAUAGAGUGAUUUUUUUUUAUUCCAUGCUACCAGUUGGUCAUGCAAUUCAAAUAUUAAAUACUAGAUUACAGAUAUUAGAAUCUUGUAAUGCAUCUGGUUUAAUACCUGUCAUUUUGUAGAACGGUUAAAUGUCUUCCCAAGGUCAUACACCUAAUCAGUGGUAUAUUCAAAACCCAAAUCCUAGGCUUCCUAUCUGAAGUCCAUUGCUUAUGAAGUGGUUUGCUAUGUGUUCUGACUUUGUUGAUUCAAAUAAGUAAGCUAAAUCAAUUUAAGCCAUUAAUAGGUUUAUAAAGUUAUUUGCUAUGUGUUGUUCUUACAUCAUUGAUUCAUGUAAGUAGACUUGUGUGACAGCUAAUUCUUAAAAAAUUAUGAAGAUGUUAGACUUCUUUUGAUAUAUAUAUGUUGAUUGUAUGAACAGAUUGACAUCAAUAUACUUAUUCAUUAUAAAAGAUUUGAGUGGGAACUCACCAAAUCCCACACCAAAAAAAUUUAAAAUUUUACCAUAGUAAAAAAAACUAAAAAGCAAGAUGAAAUUAUACAUAGUUCUUGGUGUAGUAUUUUUAAUUUUUAUUAUUUAUUUUUAUAGAAAUGGGGUCUCACCAUUUUGCCAGGCUGUUCUCAAACUCCUGGCCUCAGGUGAUCCGCCUGCCUCGACCUCCCAAAGAGCCAGGAUUAUAGGCAUGAGCUACCAUGCCCGGCUAGUGUAGUAUUUUUAAAUUUUACUUAAUGCUGAGCCAUUUUCAAAUAACCUCAUCACAUUGAUUAUGACCUCAUGCAAGAACCAUCUGUUCUAUCUUUCAGUGUAGUUGUACUUUAAUAUCUUAGAAGCUAUUGCAUUCUGUCCUUUUUUGGAAUGUUUUAUGCUUUUACAGUCUUAACCAUUGCUUCUUAAUAUCACUUCCGCGGAACAGCUGGUGCAAAGAACAUGUGAUAAGGAAUGGAAAACAAUUGAUGAUGGAAACAGAGAUUUGGAGUUAAUUGCGUUCUUAAAAUAUUAUGAUGUUCUUUCUAAUAAAAUGUACAUUUCACAUAAUUUUCCUCUUUCAGAACUAACCAUGGUUAAUCAUUCUUUAAACCAGGUUUGUUUCCGACAAAAGAAAUGAAAUAAUAAAAACUAAAUUCUAACUGUAGUAAUCAUGUGAUAUUAAAGAUAUUAUUUAUGGGGUUAAAAGCCCUCUUUAUCUUGCUUAGGGGUUUCCAAUAAUCGAAUCAGUGCUGGACUUUUUUUUUUUUUUUUUAGGCAUGGCUGCCCCCUGUUAAUAAUAUAUUUAAUUAACAGCUUUACACAAUGAUCUUAAUAUACUUGAAAUACUUAGAGGACUGCAGUUUAUAAAAUCAAGAGUCUACCUUAUUGCUGUUUUAUUUUUUUUUUUACCAUAACCCUCAGAAGGAAUACAGUUAACAUCACAGUCCUAUAUAUAAAUGUGUGUUUAUGUGUGCCAUCAUAAACAUCACUGCACUAGGUGGCAAUCUUCACUACUAUUCAUUUGUGUAUGUGUAGUCAACCUACGAAAGGAAUCAUUAGAAACAGGGUAGGAAUGUUGAACCUUAGAACCGGAAGUUGCCAGAGAAAAUAUGUGCCCUGGCCAACUCCACAGGACUAGUUCUAGGCAAUCUGAAGGAAACCAGAAAAUGUGAAUUUCUCUUCCCUCAAAAAGCUAUACUGAAGUAGUAUUUAAUAUUCAAGUACUUGUAAAUUUGCAGAACAGUACUUUUUAAUUUGACCCAUGAAUUCUAUUUAAAUUUGUCACUUAAUAUUUAGCCAAGAAGCAAACCAUCUAAAAAGAUUUCUGGUUUAUUUCUCCAACUCCUAAUAAAUAGGGUCACAUAUUUUUUAACUUUUUUCUAAUUUGAAAAGUAAUACAGGCAUAUGGUAUUUUAAAAAUGAAACAACACAAAGGGAUAUGUUUUGAAAAGUGGUUCUUGCCAUCCCUGAACUGUAAUCAUCCCUAACAUAUUCAUACCUGUUUUCAUUUUAAAAGUUGGGUCAGUUUUUUUAUUAGUACAUGUAUUUCUAUCCUACUGAUUUAUUUGCUAUAUCAUCUAAUUUAGUUUGAAUAUUCCAUAAUUUACUUAAUUAGUCCUGUAUGGAGACCUAGCUCUUCUCAGUGUCUACUAUUAUAAACAAUGCUACAGUGAAUAUUGUUGUAUAAAUCCAUACACACCACGUAACAUAUCUUAAGUUCCUGGAAGAGAUAUUGCUAAACCAGAAGAUAACCUGCAUUUAAAAUUUUGACUGCUAGGGUCAGGGUCACAUUUAAAUUAAAUUAGAACAAAGGAAUUGCAUAAUUGUCUUCGAUAGCAAUCUAUUCCAGUGUGCACCGUGAGUCACAAAGGAAAGCAAAACUGUCAAUAACUUUCUUCUCAGACUUUUGGUUUAAUGUGUUCUGAUGGGUUAAUAAUUUGUCUCAUUUCUCUUCAUAAUAAUGACUUUGAGAAUAUUUGUACUGCACUCUUUUUCCAGAAUUAACCACAACUUUUCACAGUAACUGAAUUAAUGCCACAAUGGUACAUUCAACCAGUGGGGCUUCAGGAUGUGAAAUAGACAAUAUUCUGGGCCACUGUUACUACCAAAUACUUUCUUUACCUUUAAGUCUGUAUAUUUUUAUCUGUAAAGUGACAUCCAUAGAUGUCACUGUACACUUCAUAGAAAUGAGUACACAGAAUAAUACUCAUGGCAGGGCUGGGUGUGGUGGCUCAUGCCUGUAAUCCCAGCACUUUGGGAGGCUGAGGCAGGCAGAUCACUUGAACCUGGGAGGCAGAGGUUGCACUGAGCUGAGAUCUCGCCACUGCGCUCCAGCCAGCGUGACAGAGCGAGACCCUGUCUCAAAAAAAAAAAAAAAAGGAAUAAUACUUAUGGCAGCACUGGCCACACUAUAAAAUUCAGGUUCAGAAAAACAGGGUAAGUCACAGACAGCAACGCUUCCAGCAUUUAUUUUCUUUGCACCCAUGGGCAAUUUGAGAAAAUUUACCUUUAGAACGAACUCUGUUAAAGGUACAGACAAUACAGUACUUUUUAUUCAGAAGGUUUCUGCAUAAAGGUGAUAGUCUUUUGACUUAAUAUAUUAUUGUCUCCUGCCUUGUGUUUCUGGAAUGAAUGAAGGUCAUUAUUUAGAGGAUAAUCUGGGUUGUAUUUGUGUCGUCAGAUUGAAUUUUCAUUGCACAUGCUACUUAAUGUCUUUACCAAAUAAUAACAAAGGGAAAGAAAACCAAAUAUAGAUGUAUAAUAAGGAAAAGCUGGCCUAUAGAAAAUACCAAACCAGAUAAUAGUAGCAAAGUUUAAGCCAAUUUUGUUUUUAAAAUGUCAUGUACGUGGAAAAAGGUUUAACUUUAGUUUUCUUUGGGUGGUGGUUAAAAGUUAUAAGUGAUUAAAAGUUUUUUUCUUUUUCUACAAUGAACAUUAUGUGACCUUGCAAUUUAAAAAGCCAACGCCCUUUUAAGAAAGUUAUGUCCAUCAGUAUUCCUCUAACUUCAUUUUCUCUCGUUUCUUCUUCCCUCACUUUUCUAAGUUUUCCUUUAUUAACCCCAUUUUUCUUUAGUUUGUUUGCAUGCUUCCUUGCUUUUCUUUUUUUUUUUCCUGGGUAUGAUAGAGAAUUAGUCCCAUUCUCUAAGUAUGUAAAUCAAGGAGUGAAUUUUCAAGUAGACAAAAAUGAUUUACAGCAUCCUUGCAUUCGCUACCGAUCUCUGCUUUUGUUAGCUCUUGUUUUUAGCUGGGAAAAAGCCAAUUACCGCCAUUUUAACGUUUCAGGUGUUCUUAAUUCAUUUUGAAACGCUGACUGAUGAAAAAAAUAAGGAAUAUCCUCUAUGAAUUAUCCUGAACUGGCUUAUAAUAUAUUGUUUGAAUUCCUGUUAUGAGCUUCUGUUUCUUUAACAAUAUUUUGUAAAGUGUGUUUCACAUAACAGCAGAUAAUCACCAGAAUGGGAGUGAAUGACUUGUGGCAAAUUUUGGAGCCUGUUAAGCAACACAUCCCCUUGCGUAAUCUUGGUGGGAAAACCAUUGCAGUUGAUCUGAGUCUCUGGGUGUGUGAGGCACAGACAGUCAAAAAAAUGAUGGGCAGCGUCAUGAAGCCCCACCUCAGGAACUUAUUUUUUCGUAUCUCAUAUUUAACACAAAUGGAUGUAAAACUGGUAUUUGUUAUGGAAGGGGAACCACCAAAGCUGAAAGCUGAUGUCAUAAGCAAGAGGAAUCAGUCUCGGUAUGGGUCUUCUGGAAAAUCGUGGUCUCAGAAAACAGGGAGAUCACAUUUUAAAUCAGUCUUAAGAGAGUGCCUCCAUAUGCUCGAAUGCUUAGGAAUCCCCUGGGUUCAGGCUGCUGGGGAAGCUGAAGCCAUGUGUGCUUAUCUCAAUGCUGGUGGUCAUGUCGAUGGCUGCCUCACCAAUGAUGGAGAUACUUUCCUUUAUGGGGCCCAGACUGUUUACAGGAAUUUCACUAUGAAUACAAAGGACCCACAUGUUGACUGUUACACAAUGUCAUCUAUCAAGAGUAAACUAGGUUUGGAUAGAGAUGCUCUGGUUGGAUUAGCAAUACUUCUUGGCUGUGAUUAUCUCCCAAAGGGAGUCCCUGGAGUUGGAAAAGAGCAAGCAUUAAAACUUAUACAGAUUUUGAAAGGGCAAAGUUUACUUCAGAGGUUUAAUCGGUGGAAUGAAACAUCUUGUAACUCUAGUCCACAACUGCUAGUCACUAAAAAACUGGCUCAUUGUUCCGUAUGUUCCCAUCCAGGUUCACCUAAGGAUCAUGAACGUAAUGGAUGCAGAUUAUGUAAAAGUGAUAAAUAUUGUGAGCCACAUGACUAUGAAUACUGCUGUCCUUGUGAGUGGCACCGUACAGAACAUGAUAGGCAACUCAGUGAAGUAGAGAACAAUAUUAAGAAGAAAGCUUGCUGUUGUGAGGGAUUCCCAUUCCAUGAGGUUAUUCAAGAAUUCCUUUUAAACAAGGAUAAAUUGGUGAAGGUUAUCAGGUACCAAAGACCUGAUUUGUUAUUGUUUCAGAGAUUUACUCUUGAAAAAAUGGAGUGGCCCAAUCACUAUGCAUGUGAGAAAUUGCUGGUACUUUUGACCCAUUAUGACAUGAUAGAAAGAAAGCUUGGUAGCAGAAACUCUAAUCAACUACAGCCAAUUCGAAUUGUUAAGACUCGAAUCAGAAAUGGAGUUCAUUGUUUUGAAAUAGAAUGGGAAAAGCCUGAACAUUAUGCUAUGGAAGAUAAACAACAUGGAGAAUUUGCUUUAUUAACAAUUGAGGAAGAAUCAUUGUUUGAAGCAGCAUAUCCUGAGAUCGUUGCUGUUUACCAAAAACAAAAGUUAGAAAUUAAAGGGAAGAAACAAAAACGUAUUAAGCCUAAAGAAAACAAUUUGCCAGAACCAGAUGAAGUAAUGAGCUUUCAGUCACACAUGACUUUAAAACCCACAUGUGAAAUCUUUCAUAAGCAGAAUUCCAAGUUAAAUUCGGGGAUUUCCCCUGAUCCUACAUUACCACAGGAAUCUAUUUCUGCCUCAUUGAAUAGCUUGCUUUUACCUAAAAAUACUCCAUGUUUGAAUGCACAAGAACAGUUCAUGUCUUCUCUAAGACCUUUGGCUAUACAGCAAAUUAAAGCUGUCAGUAAGUCUCUAAUUUCAGAAUCUAGUCAACCCAAUACCUCAUCUCAUAAUAUAUCCGUGAUUGCUGAUCUACACUUGAGCACUAUUGACUGGGAAGGUACUUCUUUUAGUAAUUCUCCAGCUAUUCAAAGGAAUACUUUUUCUCAUGAUUUAAAAUCAGAAGUUGAAUCAGAGCUAUCAGCCAUCCCUGAUGGCUUUGAAAAUAUCCCAGAACAACUGUCCUGUGAAUCAGAAAGGUACACUGCAAACAUAAAGAAAGUGUUGGAUGAGGAUUCUGAUGGGAUUAGUCCUGAAGAGCAUCUACUUUCUGGCAUUACUGAUUUAUGUCUUCAGGAUUUGCCUUUAAAGGAACGAAUAUUUACAAAAUUAUCAUAUCCUCAGGAUAAUCUACAACCAGAUGUCAACCUGAAAACUUUGUCCAUACUUAGUGUAAAAGAAUCUUGUAUUGCUAACAGUGGUUCUGAUUGUACAUCACAUCUUUCAAAGGAUCUUCCAGGAAUUCCCUUGCAAAAUGAAUCCAGAGACUCUAAAAUUCUAAAAGGAGACCAGCUGCUUCAAGAAGACUAUAAAGUCAAUACUUCUGUCCCUUAUUCUGUCAGUAACACAGUGGUAAAGACCUGCAAUGUUAGACCACCAAAUACUGCUUUAGAUCAUAGUAGAAAAGUUGAUAUGCAAACCACUCGGAAAAUUUUAAUGAAGAAGAGUGUUUGCCUUGACAGACAUUCCUCUGAUGAACAAAGUGCCCCAGUGUUUGGGAAAGCUAAGUACACAACUCAAAGAAUGAAGCACAGUUCUCAAAAGCAUAAUUCAUCCCAUUUCAAAGAAAGUGGCCAUAACAAGUUGAGUAGCCCUAAGAUACAUAUUAAAGAAACUGAACAGUGUGUCAGAUCUUAUGAAACAGCUGAAAAUGAAGAAAGCUGUUUCCCAGAUUCAACAAAAAGUUCUCUGAGUUCUCUACAAUGUCAUAAGAAAGAAAACAACUCUGGUACUUGUUUGGAUAGCCCUCUUCCUUUACGCCAGAGAUUAAAACUAAGAUUCCAAAGCACUUGAAAUUUAAAACACUUAGGUAUAACUUAACUAUUUUAGUACUAUCAGCAAUAGCAGAGACAGAGGGAAGGUAUCUAGUUCAUGUGUGGUAAAAAUUUUAAUGUUCUCUGUGUCAUGAAACACUUGCCAUUUUAAUCAAAGUUGUAAUUUUUAAAAAGUCACCUAAAACUCUGGUUUUAAAAGAUCCUCUGUAUUGAAAACUUCUGAUAAUGUAUGUCAUUAUGUCCUUACUAUUCCUUAAUUGUAGUUUUAAAAUAUUGGUAUAGUACUUGACAGAGUAAAUACUUCAUCUGAUUGUUCAUUUUUACUUUUUCUUCCACAAGCCUCUAAAGUAUUUAUAUUCCAGCUUGUUCCCAAGAGGAUAAUUCUUUAUACUUCUCUUCAUUCUUUUAAGGCCUUGCAAGGUCUUCCGUUAUAACUCGCUUUCCUAAAAGCUAUUUUCUCCCUCAGUGUGAAGAUACCUUUAGUGUGCUCUUCCACUUUGGAAGGCCAUGCAAGGUGUUCCAUUAUAACUCUUUUUCCUAAGAGUUAUAUUCUCCCUCAGUUUGAAGAUACCUUUAGUGUGCUCUUCCACUUUUGGUGUCUUAGUCUCUUUUGAGGGGCAAAAAUAGAAAAGGAGAGAAGAUGUCAGUAUGUUUAGUAAAAAUCAUGCUCGUAAUGGCUGAAUAAACUGAGCAAAGUAACUCCUUAUGUAUCCCCAGAAGUUCACAGGUAUAUCGGGUGGAAAAAGAUUUGGAAAAUCAAAUGUAUAACCAAAAGGAUUAGAAACUAGCCCAGGAUCACGUAGCUAACUAAUAAUCCUGUGGGAAUCAGUUUUCUUGCCUGCUAAUUUUUUUAUUUUUCUAUUUUUUCCUUCUAUAGCACUUUUCCCCCUUUUGUUUUGAAUCUAUGCAAUAUUGACUUUAAUACCACCAAAUAUUAAGUCAUGCAUUAAUUUAGGUCGCACUCAAAAAUUCUAGAGAGGCAUCCAGAUUGAAAAGGAAAAUGGUGUCUGCAGAUGACAAGAUUGUAUGCAUCAAAAAUUCUAAGAAAUCCACUAGAAAACUAUUAAAACUGAUAAAGCGAGUUCAUCCAGGUCGUAGAAUACAAGACCAAUGUGCAAUGAUCAUUGCAUUUUGUUUUUGUUUGUUUGUUUUUUUUUGAGACAGAGUCUCACUCUUGUCGAGACUGGGGUGUAGUGGCGCCAUCUUGGCUCACUGCAACCUCUGCCUCCCAGGUUCACGCAAUUCACAUGCCUCAGCCACCUGAGUAGCAGGGAUUACAGGUGUGUGCCACCAUGCCUGGCUAAUUUUUAGUAUUUUUAGUAGAGAUGGGAUUUUCCCUUGUUGGUCAGGCUAGUCAUGAACUCCUGGCCUCAAGCGAUCCACCCAUCUUGGCCUCCCAGAGUGCUGGGAUUACAGGUGUGAAUCACCAUACUCAGCCUCAAUUGUAUUUCUGUACACCUCUAAAUAAAUGGAAAUACAUUCCAUGUUCAUGAAUCAGAAGACAUAAGAUGACCAUACUCCCCAAACUGAUCUACAGGUUAAAUGUAAUUCCCAUUAAUUCCAGCUGGUUUCUUUGCUGAUUCUAAAAUUCAUAUGGAAAUUUCAGGAACACAGAAUAUUAGGAAGAAUCUUGAAAGAGUUUGAAUGACCCACCCUUCCUGAUUUUAAGUAUACAGAACUACAGUAAUGAAUGUGUUGUACUGGUAUAAAGGUAGACAUAUAGGUCAAUAUAGAUCAAUGGCAUAGAAUUGAGAAUUCAGAAAAAAAGCCUUCACGUUUAUGGUCAGUUGAUUUUAAACCAGAGUGCCAAGACAAUUCAAUGGGAAAAGGAAACAGUCUUUGAACCAACUGUCUUCUGGAUCUAUUGGAUAUCUAUGUAAAAAAGAGUGACAUUUGAUUCCUACUUCACAUGAUAUUUAAGAAGUAACUUAAGAUGGAUCAAAUACCUAAAUGUAAGCUAAAGCUAUAAAACUCUUAGAAGAAAACAUAGACGUAAAUCUUUGUGACUUUGGAUUAGGCAAGGAUUUCUUAAAUAUACCCAAAGCAUAGGCAACAAAAGAGAAUACACAAACUGGACUUCAUCAAAACUAAAAACUGUUGUUUGAAAUGACACCAUCAAGAAAGUGAAAAGACAGCUUACAGAAUGGGAGAAAAUAUUUGCAAAUCAUAAAUGUGAUAAGGGACUUGUAUCUUGGUGGUAUAUAAAGAACUCGUAACUCAAUUAUAAAAAGACAACUUUGAAAUGGGCAAAAUAGCUCAACAGGCUUUUCUGCAAAGAAGAAAUACAAAUGACCAAGAAGCACAUUUAAAAAUUUUCAGUACUAUUACUCAUCAGGAAAAUGCAAAUCAAAACCACAAGACACCCAAUGUCUACAAUCAAAAAGAUAAUAACUAGUAUUGAUGAGGAUGUGGAGAAAUUGAAAUUCUCAUAACAUGCUGGUAGGAAUGUAAAAUGGGGCAGCCACUUUGGAAAAAGUCUGGUAGUUCUUCAAAUGGUUAAAUGUAGAGUUACGAUAUGAUCCAGCAAUUCCUCUCCCAGGUAUAUACCCAAGAUAAAUGAAAACUUAUAUCCACAUAAAAACCUGUGCACAAAUGUCCAUAGCAGCGUUAUUCAUAAUAGCCUAAAAGUGGAAACAAUCCCAGUUCCAGAAUGAGGAAGGGGAGAAACUAAUGUGUAUUAGCUAUUGUGUGCUAAGCAUUCAACUAGAUUAUUUACAAACCUUGUAUCAUCUCAACUCUUUAAGGACUGUAUUGCAAUGUUUUGAAUAUUCAGAGAGAAAAAAGUCGUUGCUAAAACAUUUUCCAAGGUUCUGCUUAUUCUGAUUUGUUCAGUCGUGGCUGUGAUAGUUCAGGACCAUCUAGACCAGGUAAAUAAAAUAUCUAGAGGCAUUCUUGAGAUUGUAUGAGAUGAAAAUAACAAAAUUAGUUGGGAGUGGCCAGUCUGAGUUCAUUUUGCUAUAUAGCUCAGGAGUCCCCAACCCCUGGGCUAUGGACAGGUACCAGUCCAUCACCUGUCAGGAACCGGCCUGCACAGCAGGUGUUGAGCGGCAUGCAAGCGAGAAUUACCGCCUGAGCUCUGCCUCCUGUCAGAUCAGCGGUGGCAUUAGAGUCUCAUAGGAGCAUGAACCCUAUUGUGAACUACGCAUGCGAGGAUCUAGUUUGUGCACUCCUACUGAGAAUCUAAUGCCUGAUGAUAUAAGGUGGAACAGCUUCAUCCCACAGCCAUCUCCCCCUCAUCAUCCGUGGAAAAACUGUUUUCCACGAAAGUGGUCCUCGGUGCCAGAAAGGUUGGGGACUGCUGAUAUACCUAAUAUAGGCAUAAGUGUAAAAUUAUAGUUCCUCCUCCUCAAGGAUUUCUCUGUUUUCAUUGUCCAGGUUAUACCAAUUCUUUUUAAAGCAUUCCAUGUUCUUGUUCCUUGAUGUGGUCAUGUUAUCACUUGUAAAUCAAAUCUUUUAAGUUGCUGCUUACGUAUUUGCUCAUCACUUCAUUGUCUUGUUGAGGAUGCCUUGCUUCCCUUUGAAAUACUCUGCCAAAGAUCUGCCUCCAGCUGCUAGGAUCCUGUAAUUGGUUUCUUUCUGAUGGCUCCAUGCUAAGGCCCUGCUCUGGCCUAACUGCUUUGGGCUUUGUGUAAUCAAUCUUAAGUCCUUGGCGGUUUUUCUUUUAGAUUUUUUUCCAUAUAAAAUCUCUAUCUGGCCACACAUGGUGGCCGUGCCUGUAAUCCCAGCACGCUGGGAGGCUGAGGCGGGUGGAUUGCUUGAGGCCAGGAGUUCAAGACCAGCCUGGCCAACAUGGUGAAACCCCAUCUCUACUAAAAAUACAAAAAUCAGUGGGGCCUGGUGGCGUGCACCUGUAAUCCCAGCUACUCGGGAAGCUGAGGCAGGAGAAUCGCUUGAACCUGGGAGGCAGAGGUUGCAGUGAGCUGAGAUAGUGCCACUGCACUUCACUCCAGGAUGGGCGAAAAAGUGUCUAAAAAAAAUUAAAAUUUAAAUUAAAAAAAAAUAUACAAUCUCCGUCUUCUAGAUUUUAUAAUGAGGACUCUACUUUUUCCUUUUGGGUAGCAUGGCUUGAGCCAUCUUGUCAGGCAUACCUAGCUUCAGAUUCUUUUCUGCUAACAGAUUUUCUCUGUGACCCUGGAGACAUUUUCUAACUUUUCUGAGACUCAUUUAUUCAAAUGUUUAUGUGACAGGCAUUGUGCUGGGCCCUGGAGAUACAGUGAUCAAUGGCAUCCUAUAAGGUUUUGAUAUCUGUGAAGUCACUGCCACCAUUGACACAUUCUAGGGACUCAGUAAAUUGUAGCUGUGUCCGAUACCAUCAUUUGGAAAGAGCACUAUCAGAUUUUGGAUUCAAACUGAAUGCAGCCAAGCACUGCCUUUUGGUAAAAAUGUGGACACAGUAACACUAGUAGGGGGCAGUGUGAGGGUGGGAGAUGUGUUUUCAGAAGAAGGAAACUCUAGAUUAGCAUCACACAAGGGAUCCUAACGUGGCAUUUGAGCUACUGGAAAAAAAUUGUGCUUGCUUAAAUAUAAUGUGGUAACUAAUAUUCAUCUAAUCACCUACCACAUUUUUGGAGCACCCACUUUGAGCAAGGUUCUUAGGCUUUUCUAUGUACAACAGCCAGCUGGAGGCCCAGUGAGUUUAAAAUUUUUCCAGGUCACCCAACUAGAAAAAGUUAAAGCUGGGACUAGAACUCAGAUCUCCUAAUUCAUGAGUGAAAACAAUUCUCUGUAUUUAUGUUUCCAUACAUCAUUCAGUUCUUGACUCAAAUAUCACCUCAGAGAGUCCUAAUCUUUUUAUCUCCUGACAUUAUAAAUGUUGAGUUCAGGGUUUUUUUUUUCAUUGUUUCCCAAACUAGAAUGCAGACUUGAUGAGGGCAGGGACUAAGUCCUUUCUGUUCACAGAAUUCUAGAACAGUGUUUGACACAGUAACUACUAGAUGCAUGAAUGACAAUUCUCCACAACGCCCCACCCAUGGAGCCUGUACCAGCAGUGGCUGCACUUAACCUUGCGGAAUCUGGCCUUAGUACUUCAGCAUGGCUCACAAGGCUGAGGCAGCCUGGCCCCAACUUGUCUCUUCAGCUUCAUGCAUUCAUAGUCAUGAACCUUGGCUCUAGCCACCUAAGACCAUUUGUUAUUCCCUGCACGGAUGUCUCUGCCUGAAAUGCUUGCUGCUUCCUUAUUGGCUAGAUAAACCUCAUCUAUUAAGGACCAGCUCACAUGUCAUAACUUUAUAAUCCCAAGCAGAAUUAUUUGCUCUAUACGUGUCCCCAAAGAAAUUACCCAUACAUUCAUCAGAGUAUUUAUCACAUUCAUUCAUUCGUUCCACAAAUAUUAGCUGAUGCCUGCCGUGUAGGAGGCACAAUAUUCCUUACUUAAAAAUGCCUCUAUCUCUCCCUCAGAUAAGACUAAGAUCUCUGAGCACAGGAAUCAAGUCUUAUUUCUGUUCACUUCCCCCAGAUGCCUACACAGGGUUUGACUCUUCUGCCUCACCAACUCUUACCCAUCGAGAUUCAGUGUAAACGUGGUCUUCUCUAAGAAAGUCUUCUGUUGCUUCUCUGGAUCGCUGCUAGUCCCCAUAGACUUCUAAAAUAUUAUCUGUCUAUAGUUUUGUGUUGGGUUACAUUUUUUGUUUCCCACACCAGACUAUGAACAUCCUCAGGGCAGAGAAACUAUAUUGUACUUCUGAAUUUAUAGCACCCGGCAGAGGGAUUGGCACAGAAAGUGUCCAGUGAGGCCGGGUGUGGGGGCUCACAUCAGCAGUUUGGGAGGCCGAGAUGGGCAGAUUGCCUGAGGUCAGGAGUUCGAGACCAACCUGGCCAACAUGGUGAAAUCCCAUCUCUACAAAAAAUACAAAAAUUAGCCGGGUGUGGUGAUGGGUACCUGUAAUCCCACCUACUUGGGAGGCUGAGACAAGAGAAUCACUUGAACCCGGGAGGCGGAGGUUGCAGUGAGCUGAGACCGUGCCAUUGCACUCUAGCCUGGGCAAGAAGAGCGAAACUCCAUCUAAACAAAAGAAAAAAGAAAGUGUUCAGUGAAUGGGUGCUGAUUGACUGAUGGUGAUUUCAGUCAGGGUCUUAGUUCUAAAUUUCUCUGUGGAGAGAGACCAAAUCUAACCGGGUGGAUUAGCUUGAUACCUAGUCGCCUUUAGCCACUUCAAGACGCCCUGCCAAGAUGCUUGCUUUCUGAAGGUGAAGAGUCUAAAUCAACUGCUGUUCCUGUUCUGCUGGUAGCACUUAGGGUAAAACAGCUUAAAUAGUAUUACUGAAGGCAGCCUCCUUUCAUCUAUAUAUUAACGUGGCAAUGUUUAUCACCUUCUUAACCAAGCAAAGCUUUUAUCAGGCUCAGCUAACAGCUUGCAUUAGCCUCUUUCAGGAACUUGCCACAUUGCCUAUAAACUGACAUGCUGCAGAGUCAGCCCCAGCAAUAGUCCAAAACAGUGGGACUCUUUUUGAUGAUUUCAAAAUGGAUAGUUUAGUUAGCCCCAGGCCAGAUAAAUUCACUAAGUUGCCUGUUUGGCAAUGGAGGGCAGAGUUAUCAGCAAAGUAGGCUGACCCUUCUGUGGGCAGAAUGAAUAUUUUGCUAAUGUUUAGAAGAAUUCCUUUUGUAAGCAUCAAAGAAGAACUUUAAUAAGGAUUAAGUGUCUGAGCUUCCUUAGCAUUAUUCUAUUCCAAGACCCAAAAAGGAAAAUAACCUCCCCAAAUGGUAAAAACUGCUUGUAUAUUUAGAAUUCUCUGAUCAAAGACCUAAUGAAAAGAUUCUAUAGUGUUUGCGUCAUCAUAAGUUAAAUCUUCAUCUACCACCCAACUGAUACCUGCCUUUCUGUGAGUGAAAUCAGAAACGGCUGUUCUUUAAUAAAUGCUUUCAAUCUGAAAGUCAGAAAGUGAUUUAUGAAACACCCAGGUGAGGGGAGACUACAAGUCCCUUUGCCUUUUAGUUUUCAAGCAAUACUGGUUGCAGUAACUGCUCUGAUGUAAUUAUUGCUAACAUUUACGUUUUUAUUAAACUGAAAAUGCUAACUGUGAAUGCCA